ACUUCAAAAUCCGGGUCAAAGGGUGUCGCUUCGGUCUCUUCUCCCCGGCUGAUCCCAGCACUCUCCGUGACAGCGCCUCCUGACUCAGCCCAGGACCGGCUUCUUCUCACGACCUGCUGGAGACUGGACGCCCACACCUGACCCGGAACUCGGAGGCGUGCUUCCUCCACCCGCCGGCUAGCAGCCCCGGGCCCUGAGCUCCCGCCGACGCCGCUGGGGGGCCCGACAGGCCCCUCGGCGCUGAUGCUGAGUGGGAUCGAGGGCCCGGGGCGGCGGCGGAGUACGGGCCUCUGGCGCCUUAGGCCAGCCGCAGGUGUCGGUUCUUAGGCUCUCCAGGCUCGCUAGCUCCCGCCCCGGCUUGGAUGGGUCUCCCUGCGCCAUAAAUGUGGCUGCUGAGGCGGCGGUGGCCGUGGCCCGUCGCGCUGCUGCUGCGGCGCUCCAAGUUCAUCUCCGCCCCGGGGCUCUCCUGCCCCACCUCGGGGCUGCCGCCACCCGCUCCUUAUCCCCUGGCCCUGGCCUUGCAGCGUGGCGACAAUGGACAAGAUCCUGGAGGGCCUUGUGAGUUCCUCGCAUCCCCUGCCCCUCAAGCGGGUGAUUGUGCGGAAGGUGGUGGAAUCGGCGGAGCACUGGCUAGACGAGGCGCAGUGCGAGGCCAUGUUUGACCUGACGACCCGGCUCAUCCUGGAGGGCCAGGACCCUUUCCAGCGGCAGGUGGGGCACCAGGUGCUGGAGGCCUACGCACGAUACCACCGGCCAGAGUUCGAGUCCUUCUUCAACAAGACCUUCGUGUUGGGCCUCCUUCAUCAGGGCUACCACUCUCUGGACAGGAAGGAUGUAGCCAUCCUGGACUACAUUCACAACGGCCUGAAGCUGAUUAUGAGCUGUCCGUCGGUGCUGGAUCUCUUUAGCCUCCUGCAGGUAGAGGUGUUACGGAUGGUGUGUGAGAGGCCGGAGCCGCAGCUCUGUGCCCGACUGAGCGACCUUCUGACCGACUUUGUGCAAUGCAUCCCCAAGGGGAAAUUGUCCAUCACGUUCUGUCAACAGCUGGUUCGAACGAUAGGCCAUUUCCAGUGCGUGUCCACCCAGGAAAGAGAGCUGCGGGAAUAUGUCUCCCAGGUGACAAAAGUGAGUAACUUGCUGCAGAACAUCUGGAAGGCCGAGCCUGCCACACUACUGCCUUCCCUGCAAGAAGUUUUUGCAAGCAUCUCUUCCACAGAUGCAUCAUUUGAACCUUCUGUAGCAUUGGCAAGCCUUGUGCAGCAUAUUCCUCUUCAGAUGAUUACAGUUCUCAUCAGGAGCCUUACUACGGAUCCAAAUGUAAAAGAUGCAAGUAUGACCCAAGCCCUUUGCAGAAUGAUUGACUGGCUAUCCUGGCCAUUGGCUCAGCAUGUGGAUACAUGGGUAAUUGCACUCCUGAAAGGACUGGCAGCUGUCCAGAAGUUUACUAUUUUGAUAGAUGUUACUUUGCUGAAAAUAGAACUGGUUUUUAAUCGACUUUGGUUUCCUCUUGUGAGACCUGGUGCUCUUGCAGUUCUUUCUCACAUGCUGCUUAGCUUUCAGCAUUCUCCAGAGGCGUUCCAUUUGAUUGUUCCUCAUGUGGUUAAUUUGGUUCAUUCUUUCAAAAAUGAUGGUCUGCCUUCAAGUACAGCCUUCUUAGUACAAUUAACAGAAUUGAUACACUGUAUGAUGUAUCAUUAUUCUGGAUUUCCAGAUCUCUAUGAACCUAUUCUGGAGGCAAUAAAGUCUUGCUCUGUUGCCCAGGCUGAAGUGCAAUGGCAUGAUCACGGCUCACUGCAGCCUCUACAUCUUGAGCUCAAGUGACCCUCCUGCCUCAGCCUCCCAAGUAGCUGGGACUCCAGGAUUUUCCUAAGCCCAGUGAAGAGAAGAUUAAGUUAAUUCUCAAUCAAAGUGCCUGGACUUCUCAAUCCAAUUCUUUGGCGUCUUGCUUGUCUAGACUUUCUGGAAAAUCUGAAACUGGGAAAACUGGUCUUAUUAACCUAGGAAAUACAUGUUAUAUGAACAGUGUUAUACAAGCCUUGUUUAUGGCCACAGAUUUCAGGAGACAAGUAUUAUCUUUAAAUCUAAAUGGGUGCAAUUCAUUAAUGAAAAAAUUACAGCAUCUUUUUGCCUUUCUGGCCCAUACACAGAGGGAAGCAUACGCACCUCGGAUAUUCUUUGAGGCUUCCAGACCUCCAUGGUUUACUCCCAGAUCACAGCAAGACUGUUCUGAAUACCUCAGAUUUCUCCUUGACAGGCUCCAUGAAGAAGAAAAGAUCUUGAAAGUUCAGGCCUCACACAAGCCUUCUGAAAUUCUGGAAUGCAGUGAAACUUCUUUACAGGAAGUAGCUAGUAAAGCAGCAGUACUAACAGAGACCCCUCGUACAAGUGACGGUGAGAAGACUUUAAUAGAAAAAAUGUUUGGAGGAAAACUACGAACUCACAUACGUUGUUUGAACUGCAGGAGUACCUCACAAAAAGUGGAAGCCUUUACAGAUCUUUCGCUUGCCUUUUGUCCUUCCUCUUCUUUGGAAAACAUGUCUGUCCAAGAUCCAGCAUCAUCACCCAGUAUACAAGAUGGUGGUCUAAUGCAAGCCUCUGUACCCGGUCCUUCAGAAGAACCAGUAGUUUAUAAUCCAACAACAGCUGCCUUCAUCUGUGACUCACUUGUGAAUGAAAAAACCAUAGGCAGUCCUCCUAAUGAGUUUUACUGUUCUGAAAACACUUCUGUCCCUAACGAAUCUAACAAGAUUCUUGUUAAUAAAGAUGUACCUCAGAAACCAGGAGGUGAAACCACACCUUCAGUAACUGACUUACUAAAUUAUUUUUUGGCUCCAGAGAUUCUUACUGGUGAUAACCAAUAUUAUUGUGAAAACUGUGCCUCUCUGCAAAAUGCUGAGAAAACUAUGCAAAUCACGGAGGAACCUGAAUACCUUAUUCUUACUCUCCUGAGAUUUUCAUAUGAUCAGAAGUAUCAUGUGAGAAGGAAAAUUUUAGACAAUGUAUCACUGCCACUGGUUUUGGAGUUGCCAGUUAAAAGAAUUACUUCUUUCUCUUCAUUGUCAGAAAGUUGGUCUGUAGAUGUUGACUUCACUGAUCUUAGUGAGAACCUUGCUAAAAAAUUAAAGCCUUCAGGGACUGAUGAAGCUUCCUGCACAAAAUUGGUGCCCUAUCUAUUAAGUUCCGUUGUGGUUCACUCUGGUAUAUCCUCUGAAAGUGGGCAUUACUAUUCUUAUGCCAGGAAUAUCACAAGUACAGACUCUUCAUAUCAGAUGUACCACCAGUCUGAGGCUCUGGCAUUAGCAUCCUCCCAGAGUCAUUUACUAGGGAGAGAUAGUCCCAGUGCAGUUUUUGAACAGGAUUUGGAAAAUAAGGAAAUGUCAAAAGAAUGGUUUUUAUUUAAUGACAGUAGAGUGACAUUUACUUCAUUUCAGUCAGUCCAGAAAAUUACGAGCAGGUUUCCAAAGGACACAGCUUAUGUGCUUUUGUAUAAAAAACAGCAUAGUACUAAUGGUUUAAGUGGUAAUAACCCAACCAGUGGACUCUGGAUAAAUGGAGACCCACCUCUACAGAAAGAACUUAUGGAUGCUAUAACAAAAGACAAUAAACUAUAUUUACAGGAACAAGAGUUGAAUGCUCGAGCCCGGGCCCUCCAAGCUGCAUCUGCUUCAUGUUCAUUUCGGCCCAAUGGAUUUGAUGACAACGACCCACCAGGAAGCUGUGGACCAACUGGUGGAGGGGGUGGAGGAGGAUUUAAUACAGUUGGCAGACUCGUAUUUUGAUCCUGAGAGAGUCCAAAAUGCACUGGUCACGAAACGUCUAAUACUAUGACUGUUAAAAUGUCAGACUAUAACAAAUAUCUAUCUUUUAUUUUUCAUUAGACCCUUAUACUUCAAGAGAACACACUCAGUGCUUGUUUUUAUUUUCUUGACACAUUUAUUAACAAAAUGCAUCAUGGAAAAAAAAAUCUACCUCUUAAAAUUCCAUUUGCUUUUAUGGUUAGACAUGCUUGACCAAAAAUGUUCAGAAGAAAAUAUGUACCUGGUCCCUAAUUAAGCUGCGUUAAAUUUGGUAGAAGCAUUUAAAUGGUCUAUCUUCAGUUUUACUGAACAAAAAAUGUAAUUUAUUUAGCAUUCUUUAUAAAAGAAUUGAUGCUAGAGGUAAAAAAAAAUACUUGUUUUUAAAAAAUCCUUUACGUCUUGUGUAAUUACCCCAUUAUUAAAUUCAAGUCCUUGAAAAUCAACUAGAGAUUAUAAAGUCUCUAAAGAAGGCAAUAACAAAAUUUAUCAAGAUAUAGUACUUUUCAGUUUUUGUUUAGUGUCUUCAGCAUCACUGUGUCUGUAUUUCAAGUACAAAUGUUUUUAAAAAGGAUUCUUUAUACAUAUGUGCUGAAUUGAUUUUAAGAAAGUUGCAUGAUCCUGUAGGAGCAACAUUUUUACCUAAAAAAUGCUAACUUUAUAGUAUUUCUAAUUGUUCAAGGAUUUUAAAAUUCUAUUUCAGGGAGUAUAUCUUCUGUGGUUUUGAAGGAGGUGAGUUCUGUAUGUGCCUUGCAGUACUGUAAUUCAAAAAUAGGAAUCUUUGGCUGCAAAAUUUUAAUGAAAUGUUAGGAAGUAAUUUUCGUGCUAACAUUAAAAUUAUAACUUUUUGAAAGGUAAUAGAUUUUCCAGAAGUAAAAUCUGAUGGUUCUAAAUCAAUCAAUGUGAUAGUUCAUUUUUAACUCUUAGAAGAAUUCAGAGGAAAUUAACCCAGCUAAGUAAAAAAUCUGUCUUGAUUUUGUUACUUAUUCCUCAGAAUAUUAAACAUUGAUCACAUAUUUUUAGAGUUUUACAUUUGGGUUUUUUGUUUGUUUGUUUCAGUCAUAUGUUUGGCACUGUUGUUUCUAUUUUCGUAGUUUUAGAUAAAAUGUUAAAAUGCCAAACCCUACCUUCCUACACUUUUUCUUUUGCCAGGAAACUGGAAACAUGUCAGUUCUCCUGGUUCUUGAUUAUACAGUACUCAAGAGUUAUCCCAGUUAUCCCCCUUCCUAAAGGUUUUAACUUAUCCACAGUUGUGCAUUGUUCUGAAGAUUGGUCUCAUAUUUAUUUUGAAAACACUUUAAGGAAACAAUGUUCUUCGAUGAUUUGGGGUUUAUCUUUUUCCCAAGCUUUUAUGACAGUGGUUAAAAAACAGAAAUCCUCAUGUUUAUUCCAUUACCUCCCAUUCCUAACCUGUUUCCAAUCACCAGGAAGAUUAGGAAGGCAGAUUAGAUUAAAAACUGAAAAUUCUUUGCAGAUUUAAUGAAGGUUCUCCUCCUUAUAAAUGAAUGAACCAGUUAUCAUGCUUUUCUGUGGUUUUCCUAUCCCAAUAGUGAAUUUCUGAGCUAUCCUGUGUGUUCAGUUAUCCACUUACUUGAUAGCAACUUACGACCAGAUUAUAUCAGUCUUGGCAUUUAUUGAAAUUGGUAAAGUGAUUUAAUACUUGAUAGAUUGAUAUUGGGCUAAGAUGCUUCUAGGAACUUUCAUAAAAGCAAUUAUACUUGUGCAGCUUUAUCUAUGAAUAUCAGGUCUCUCAAGGAUUUUAUGUAUCAAGAUAAUAUGUAUUGACUUUUUUAAAUGAUAAAAUGAAUUCUAGUUAGAGUCUUUCCUUGGUAUCUGCAGUGGAUUGGUUCCAGAACACCAUCCCCCAAUAUUAAAAUCCACAGAUACUCAAGUCCCUUAUUUAUAUAAAAUAGCACAGUAUUUGCAUAUAACCUGUGCACAUCCUCCCAUAUACUUUAAUCUCCAGAUGAUUAGAUAUGAUUGCAUAGCACUUACGUUGUGCUAUGUAGUUGUUAUAUUGUUUUUUCAUUUGUACUAUUUUUUAUGAUAUUUAUUGGUUUUUUAAAUUUUCUAUCCAAAGUUGUUUGAAUCUAAGGAUACAGAGCCUGAGGAUAUGGAAAGCUGACUAAAUAUAGUAACACUGAAGAGUAUUCAAAUGAUAACUCAUACCAGUACCAAAAACUUGAAGACUUCCUUUUAACAUUAAAAAUACAGUAACUUUUUACGUGAUUUGUUGAAUUCAACAUAUUUGGAACCAGAAUAAUCAGAAACUUCAUUCAAAACCUAUGCAUCUGAACUUUUUUAGUAAGGUAAUACUCAGGACUGUUCUGAUUCUAACAGAUCCCUGUUAAUUACAGAUUUAUUUGUCAUAUUAGGUCUUUUCUUUCUCCCAUAUUCCUAACCCGUGUACUAGCUCCAACUGUUGUGAGGUUUGACUCUGAAGACUGAGUAGAGUACUAUUGUUGUUUUUCUUUCCUUAGUCAGAGUAAUCAGUUUAAAUGAAGUUGCUCAUUGCUGCUAAGAAGCAUUAGGCUUCACUGCUAGCAAAAAUGAAAAACUACAAAUCUGAGUCUUUCUUUCAAAGAUGUUUAUUGACAUAAUUAAAGUAAAAAAUUGUUUAGAGAUAUGCAAAGAAGGAAAUAUAUAUGAUGUCACACAAGCUCCAGUAAGCUAUCCACUAAGCAGGUGCCUGUGCAACUCUGAUUUAUGGCAUUAACAUAUCAAAUUGAAGGAAGGAUUCUAGCUCAUUUUCCAUUCAAGCAUCUUCCCACUGCCUCUCUUCCAGCUAAAUAAUCAGAGAAGCAGGGCAGUAUAUCCCUGGAGAUCCCUGACUUUUAUCUCCAUACCUUAAAUUGUUGGUAGAUCCUUUGGAUGUAGAGAUAAAAAUUCAUUAUGAUGCUAGAGGCAUUGGGGGGUCCAUGCGAAAGGUUCAAACAGCCUAUUACAUUAAUGCACAUGUGGAAAGAACAAAAAUUUUCAAGCUAAGUCUUAAGUUCAAAUCUAUAAUUUUUUUCUCUUCAGUUCUGUUCUUUGUAUGAUAAUCCUUAAAAAAGUAGUUGUCUUCUUUUCACAUACACCUCUUUAAAGCUAUCAUCUUAUAAUAAGUGGAAUUGGAUGCUUAUUGUGUGCCCAGCACAGUUUAGGAAAAAAAUAAUUGGCACUGUUUGUCCAGUUACUGGAGAUCUUCAUUUUGAUGCUUUGUACUUUGUUCCAGGUCUUUAAUUCUCAGUCCAUCUUUUCCUAUGAUUGUGUACUUCACAUGAUACAUUCCAUAUAAAGAGCUCUUUUAAAAUGACUAUUUCAAAAAUACUGUACAUUUAUAUAUAGUAUUUUUUCUCAUAAAAAUGUGAUAGUUUAUAUAUCCUUUCAUCAUACGUUUUUUCUAAUGAGUUUAGAUUUCUGA